GUAGAGACGGGGUACAGCUCAAACCUAUUUGUUUGGGAGUUCUGUCACUUCAACCCCAAAUGUUCCAGCUAAUAUGGUGGUGGAGGGGUUUUUGGCAAAUCAUCUUAAGUGCAGUAGAGAAGUUGGACGAAAAACAGCCCAGUUAAGAGGCCGAUGGACAGCCAACUUCAGAGUGGCCUCUGCAAGCUUGGACCUCGGGGUAGACAGUGGGGCGCUCUCUAGGGGUCAUCUGUUCCCUGCUGGGGUAGGGGGGAGGCAUGUCCACGGAGGCCAGGGCUGUGGGUUCGGCACUAGGUCCUCCUCCCCGUGGCUUCCUAGUAGGCAUGUGGUGGUGUACGCCUGCUGGGCACCUAGCGAGAGGGGUCGUGAGUUGGGAGGGAGCCACGUUGGGGUGCCUGCCUGCUCGGGGGCCCCUGCCCACUGCGUGUGCGCAGCGCCUGUCAGGAUGUGACGGGGACCUGGACAUGUGUGUGCUCUCCGAGCUGAGCUGUGUGCGCGUCCGGGUUCUCGACCUCAGCUGCCUGGCUGUGCAUCCAGCGUGCACGACCGGUGUGGCCUGGGCUCCAGCCUGGAGUGUGGACCGGGUCGGCCGGCGUGUGCCUCCCCUGUGAGGGUGCCCUGGCGGGUGUGAGCCCGGCGGGCUGGAGAACCGGGUCUCGGCGCCGCAGGUCCCGCGCGGCCCCGGGUGAGGCACGCCCGCGCGCCCGCCGGCGCCAUGGGAAGGAGCGGGCGCCGCUGCUGUCCCCCGCCGGCGCGCGCACGACUUGAGACCUGCCACGGGCAGCCCCCGGCCGCGGGUCCCCGAGUGACGCUGGCGGCACCUGAGAGUGUGGCGCGGGCCCGGGGCCACGCAGCGGAGCCCAGUGUCCAGUGAAGCGUCUGAGGACCCGCCGCCCGUGCCGCCGCCAUGGUGAUGUCCCAGGGCACCUACACGUUCCUCACGUGCUUCGCCGGCUUCUGGCUCAUCUGGGGUCUCAUCGUCCUGCUCUGCUGCUUCUGCAGCUUCCUGCGCCGCCGCCUCAAACGGCGCCAGGAGGAGCGACUGCGCGAGCAGAACCUGCGCGCCCUAGAGCUGGAGCCCCUCGAACUCGAGGGCAGUCUGGCCGGGAGCCCCCCGGGCCUGGCGCCGCCGCAGCCACCACCACACCGUAGCCGCCUGGAGGCGCCGGCUCACGCGCACUCGCAUCCGCACGUGCACGUGCACCCGCUGCUGCACCACGGGCCCGCGCAGCCGCACGCGCACGCGCACCCACACCCGCACCACCACGCGCUCCCGCACCCGCCGCCUACGCACCUGUCGGUGCCGCCACGGCCCUGGAGCUACCCGCGCCAAGCGGAAUCGGACAUGUCCAAACCACCGUGUUACGAAGAGGCGGUGCUGAUGGCAGAGCCGCCGCCGCCCUAUAGCGAGGUGCUCACGGACACGCGCGGCCUCUACCGCAAGAUCGUCACGCCCUUCCUGAGUCGCCGCGACAGCGCGGAGAAGCAGGAGCAGCCGCCUCCCAGCUACAAGCCGCUCUUCCUGGACCGGGGCUACACCUCGGCGCUGCACCUGCCCAGCGCCCCUCGGCCCGCGCCGCCCUGCCCAGCCCUCUGCCUGCAGGCCGACCGUGGCCGCCGGGUCUUCCCCAGCUGGACCGACUCAGAGCUCAGCAGCCGCGAGCCCCUGGAGCACGGAGCUUGGCGUCUGCCGGUCUCCAUCCCCUUGUUCGGGAGGACUACAGCCGUAUAGAGGGGCGCCCGGCGCCCCGGGCCCCACCGGCGGACUCCUGGCCUGACUGCGGGGCUUUUUAAAUGCUUCCCUGGACUGCGGGGAGGGGCGGGGGGAGGGAGGGAUUUCUUAUCCCGUUUGUUACAUUUUGAGGAUAAUAAAGGUGUGUGAUCUGGUUUGGUACAA